CAGGUGCUGGGAGCAGGGAGAGAGGCCAGGGAGUGGGAGCAGGCACUUCCGAGCCUGUGGGGAAAGAGGGUCUUCCCGGGUAGCUGAGAGUACAGGAAUGCCCAGGUCUGGAGCCUCUGCUGGCUGCAGCUGUGCCAGGAGCCCCGCCAACUUGGUAGGGGGCAGCGCUCCCGCUUGUUUUCUGCCCUGCUGGCUCCAUGGAGGGCGCAGCCCUGGCCGCGCCUCCCCGGAUGCAUCCAGACAGGCUGCGGCUGCCAUCAAUAAUGCUUAUUUAUUAGCGCUGCAGUUUGGUAUGUAUACAAACAAAUGCCCUGAAAUGUAGCUGAAGAAGUUGUCUCUGGGUGGUGGGAUAGGUGAUGAUUUUUUUUCUUUGAUUUUAUAGUACAUGUUAUUUAAAAAUCACUGCCUUACUGAUUAGUUCCACGUAUAAUUUCUGAAGGGGACACUGUAACAGAAAGGUUUAGAGCAGGGGCUAAGCGUCAGGCUGACCUGGUUUUUGGUAGCAGCCUUGAUCCGAUCCAUUGUAUGACCUGACCAUGUUUUACUUUUCUCAGCAUUUGUUUCCUCAUCUGUAAAGUGAGACUCCUUAAACUUAACUCAGAGUUGUCAAGAUUAGAAAUGAUAAUGUAUUAUAAUAGCCUUUAAAAAAUAAAUUUCUUAUUUUGCUUUAAUUCUUGCAAUAAAAACAGUAUCGCACUGUUGCCUGGGCUGGAGUGCCGUGGUGCGAUCUUGGCUCGCUGCAACCUUCACCUCCUAGGUUCAAGUGAUUCUCCUGCCUCAGCCUCCUGAGUAGCUGGGACUACAGGCGCGUGCCACCAUGCCUGGCUAAUUUUUGUAGAGAUGAGGUUUCACCAUGUGGGCCAGCUGGUCUCGAACUCCUGACCUCAGGCGAUCUACCCUCCCCAGCCUCCCAAAGUGCUGGGAUUACAGGCAUGAGCCACCACGUCCAGCCAAAAACAAGUCAACUUUUUUUGCCUUCCAUUGAAUGUAUCAUAACAAAGACAUUCAAGAUGCAAUAGUCAAAACUCAAAUGAAUUUGGAGGCUAAACUAUUAAGUGUAUAAUUACUCUGUGAGUUACAGAUUGAGUGUAAGUUUCACUAAAAUAAAUUGUAAAUGAUAAUAAUGAAAAUGUAAUUUUAAUUUUCUGCCAAGACAAAUAUUGUUUUCAUUCUUGAUAAUCUUCACCUGUCGAACUACCACAAAUGUUACGUUUAUUACCACGUAUAUAACCUUUUGCAAUCUGGGCCACACAAGAGAAUAAACCCUGUCCUUAGGCAUCCGUUGCAUGUAAUGAAUUUGCUUCUCUCUUGUGUGUCUAGAAUGGAACCAGCUUGUGUCAUCUAAUUUCUCAUAUGGAAGAAGUGAGAAAACUGUCACCCAAAACAAAUCACUGUUCUGUGGUUUAGAUGAGGAACCCUGAUUGAGAUGCCUGGCACGUAGAAGGCACUCAAACGGAAACAGUUCCUAUUGUAUUUGUCCUGGAAGUCAGAUAAAAGAGCAGUUGCUUUCCGGAUUUCUUUGUUUGGUAUAAGCAUCUUCGGGAAAAUGUAUUUUCCAGAGUGUGAUCCAGUAAGUGGACAGCUCUGUGGCAAUUUCUUAGGCCCUGUCUUUGGAUCCUGUGCUGUAGGACCACACGCAGCUCCUCCGUUUGUCCUCUUGUAGUGUAAUGGCCCUGUUCCUCCACUGUAGGGCGCCAAGGUACUGCUUCCUAUCUGGGAAGAGUUUUCUGAAUGUUACUGCUUUCCCCUUAACUGUCCGAAGCCUUAUUGUAUCCCAAGCCUUAUUCAGGCCUCACAUUUAAUACUUUGUCACAAAUUGCUUUAUGCUACUGAUCUACUUCUUGCCUGGAAUCCCAUUUGUUUGGGGUUGGUAGAAGGUGUUAUUGGGAAAAUUCAACUUCAUUCAGAUCUUCCAUGGUGGCUUAUUCUAAUUCGGCAGAAAGCAUUGGUGGGCAAACUCCCAGGAGACCAUGAGGUCUGUAAAGUUACCAAAAUUGCUGUGCUCUCACUUUCUGAAAUGGAACCUCAGGAUCUUGAGCUAGAGCUCUGUAAGAAGCAUCAUUUUGGUAUUAACAAACCAGAGAAGAUCAUACCAUCUCCUGAUGACUCAAAGUUUCUACUGAAGACCUUUACGCAUAUUAAAUCCAAUGUGUCUGCUCCUAAUAAAAAGAAAGUUAAGGAAAGUAAAGAGAAGGAGAAGUUGGAGAGGAGAUUACUUGAAGAGUUGCUGAAGAUGUUCAUGGACUCAGAAUCCUUUUAUUAUAGCUUGACCUAUGACCUGACCAAUUCCGUGCAGAGGCAGAGCACUGGGGAGAGGGACGGUCGGCCCCUCUGGCAGAAGGUUGAUGACCGAUUUUUUUGGAAUAAAUACAUGAUACAAGAUCUUACUGAGAUUGGUACUCCAGAUGUGGACUUUUGGAUUAUCCCCAUGAUCCAAGGUUUUGUGCAGAUUGAAGAACUUGUGGUUAAUUAUACCGAAUCAUCUGAUGAUGAGAAAAGCAGCCCAGAGACCCCCCCUCAGGAGUCCACCUGUGUAGAUGAUAUUCACCCACGAUUUCUAGUGGCUCUCAUUUCACGCCGAAGUAGGCACAGAGCAGGAAUGCGCUAUAAACGAAGAGGAGUGGAUAAAAAUGGAAAUGUUGCCAAUUAUGUGGAGACUGAGCAGUUGAUUCAUGUUCAUAAUCAUACCCUGUCAUUUGUUCAAACACGAGGCUCUGUGCCUGUCUUUUGGAGCCAGGUUGGGUAUCGAUAUAACCCAAGACCGCGGCUGGACAGAAGUGAAAAGGAAACUGUUGCCUAUUUCUGUGCCCAUUUCGAAGAACAACUGAACAUUUACAAAAAACAGGUUAUUAUUAACUUGGUAGACCAGGCAGGAAGAGAGAAGAUUAUUGGCGAUGCUUACCUGAAGCAAGUGUUGCUUUUCAACAACUCACACCUCACUUACGUUUCGUUUGACUUCCAUGAGCACUGCCGAGGAAUGAAGUUUGAGAAUGUUCAGACACUAACAGAUGCCAUUUAUGACAUUAUUCUUGAUAUGAAGUGGUGUUGGGUUGAUGAAGCUGGGGUAAUAUGUAAGCAGGAAGGGAUUUUUCGUGUUAAUUGUAUGGACUGCCUGGAUCGCACCAACGUGGUCCAAGCUGCCAUCGCGAGAGUGGUCAUGGAACAGCAGCUGAAAAAAUUAGGUGUGAUGCCCCCGGAACAGCCAUUACCUGUGAAAUGUAAUCGCAUCUACCAGAUAAUGUGGGCCAAUAAUGGUGACUCCAUUAGCAGACAGUAUGCUGGGACAGCUGCUCUGAAGGGUGACUUUACAAGGACAGGAGAAAGGAAGUUAGCAGGAGUUAUGAAAGAUGGAGUGAACUCAGCAAACAGAUAUUACCUCAACCGAUUUAAGGAUGCUUAUAGGCAAGCUGUUAUAGAUUUGAUGCAAGGCAUUCCAGUGACAGAAGAUCUUUAUUCCAUAUUUACCAAGGAGAAAGAACAUGAAGCUUUGCAUAAGGAAAAUCAGAGAAGCCACCAGGAACUAAUUAGCCAGCUCUUACAAAGUUACAUGAAGUUACUACUGCCUGAUGAUGAGAAGUUCCAUGGGGGCUGGGCCCUCAUUGACUGUGACCCUAGCCUCAUUGAUGCUACUCACAGAGACGUGGAUGUGCUGUUACUGCUUUCUAACUCUGCCUACUACGUGGCCUAUUAUGAUGAUGAAGUUGAUAAAGUAAACCAGUAUCAACGACUAAGUCUAGAAAACCUGGAAAAAAUUGAAAUAGGCCCUGAACCCACUCUUUUUGGUAAGCCAAAGUUCUCCUGCAUGCGACUGCACUACAGAUACAAAGAAGCGAGUGGCUAUUUCCACACAUUGCGAGCUGUAAUGCGUAAUCCUGAAGAGGAUGGAAAAGAUACCCUUCAGUGCAUUGCAGAGAUGCUGCAGAUCACCAAGCAAGCCAUGGGAUCGGAUUUACCCAUAAUUGAGAAGAAACUUGAGAGGAAGAGCAGUAAACCUCACGAAGACAUCAUUGGUAUCAGGUCUCAAAACCAAGGUUCUUUGGCCCAGGGAAAGAAUUUUUUAAUGAGCAAAUUUUCAUCUCUAAAUCAAAAAGUGAAGCAGACCAAAUCCAAUGUAAAUAUUGGCAACCUCCGAAAGCUAGGAAACUUUACCAAACCUGAAAUGAAAGUUAACUUUCUAAAACCAAACUUAAAAGUAAAUCUUUGGAAAUCAGAUAGUAGUCUUGAAACUAUGGAAAACACAGGAGUGAUGGAUAAGGUUCAGGCAGAGUCUGAUGGGGACAUGUCUUCAGAUAAUGACUCAUACCACUCUGAUGAAUUCCUUACAAAUUCUAAGUCUGAUGAAGACAGGCAGCUAGCUAACUCAUUAGAGAGUGUAGGGCCAAUAGAUUACGUUCUUCCUAGUUGUGGUAUUAUUGCCUCAGCGCCUCGAUUGGGCAGUCGGUCCCAGUCUCUUAGCAGCACAGAUAGUAGCGUUCAUGCUCCUUCAGAGAUUACUGUUGCUCAUGGGAGUGGGCUUGGAAAAGGCCAGGAGUCUCCUUUGAAGAAAAGUCCUUCUGCUGGCGACGUACACAUAUUGACUGGCUUUGCCAAGCCUAUGGAUAUUUACUGCCACAGAUUUGUGCAAGAUGCACAGAACAAAGUGACCCACCUAUCAGAGACCAGAUCUGUGUCUCAGCAGGCUAGUCAGGAAAGAAAUCAAAUGACCAAUCAAGUUUCAAAUGAAACCCAAUCAGAAUCAACAGAACAGACACCUUCUCGGCCAUCGCAAUUAGAUGUCUCUCUUUCUGCAACAGGCCCACAGUUUUUGUCAGUUGAGCCAGCGCAUUCAGUUGCAUCUCAAAAAACCCCCACCUCCGCUUCCAGCAUGCUUGAACUUGAGACAGGGCUUCAUGUAACUCCUUCUCCUUCAGAGAGCAGUAGCAGCAGAGCAGUCUCUCCCUUUGCCAAGAUUCGAAGUUCCAUGGUCCAGGUUGCUAGUAUUACCCAAGCUGGAUUAACCCAUGGGAUAAACUUUGCAGUGUCAAAAGUUCAGAAGAGUCCUCCAGAACCUGAAAUCAUUAAUCAAGUCCAGCAAAAUGAACUUAAAAAGAUGUUUAUACAAUGCCAGACACGGAUAAUUCAGAUUUAGCUUUUAGCCAUAAGAAUCCUUCCAUGGCUUUUAUUUAAAAAUAUGAAAUUUUCACCUCUUGGGGUAUUUUAAUUGUACUGUCUGAACCCAGGGAUCACAAAUUCUGUUCAUUGGAAAGGGUUUUAAACGGAGUCGGAACCUGAGUAGAUUUCCAAAUUUUACAGCCAGGACUACAGAAGUGCAUCAUUCUAGAAUGUGUAGACCUGAGUAGCUUAUACACUACAGAGCACUUUGCUUAUUUGAAAGUAAUUCAGCAACAGGUCACUUUGGGAUAUAACCUGAACCUUUUUUUGGAGUGGGGUGGGUAGACUACAGUAGACACAAGGGCUGGACAUGCAGAUGCUUAGGGGAUUAGCGUUUUUCAUAAUUUGUUCUGUUUGUCAGUUCAUUCCUGUGUGUUCUUACCUCUACAAAGUAAAUUACACAUUUAGUUUUUAGUGACUUUAACAUGUUACUGAAGCAUUUGAAUAUAAAGCUAUUUUAGUUUUGAUGGCUUAACUGUUCCCUGAGGAGUUGAGGGUUAUUGACACUAGAGAAAUGAAUUCUCAUUUGAUCCUAAUUUUCCCCGUAUUCUACUUGAACACAUUAAAAAUACUCUGCUGCCUAUACAAUGUAAACCUAGGAGCAUUAAGACUUGUCACACAGUAAACCUGAUACAUCAGAGGUGAAUACCAGCACCUAUUAGGUUUCAUUUUGCUGUUUUCAGGAAUGUAAGAACACCCAUAUUGGCUACUGGAAAUUCUAGAAGUCAGUCAGGUUUUAAUUUAUUCCAGGAGGGGCAUCCUCGACAUCUUAUGUAGAUGAUCCACAACUUCAAAAUUUAGUCUGGGCCUAGUGCAGUGGCUCACACCUAUAAUCCCAACACUUUGGGAGGCCAGGAGUUUUGAGACCAGCCUGGGAAACAUCUGUCUCUACAAAAAAAUACAAAAAUUAGCUGGGCAUAGUGGUGCAUGCCUGUGUUUCUAGCUACGCAGGAGGAUUGCUUGAGCCCAUGAGAUUGAGGCUGCAGUGAGCUGUGAUCGUGCCACUGACCUCCAGCCUGGGGGACAGAGCAAGACCGUGUCUCAAAAACAAUUUAGUCUGAAACACAAUUGUGCUGAAUCUGUCUGACUAUAACUCUGACCACACAGAACCAGGGCUGCCCCUGUAAUCCCCACAGUAAGAAAGUUGUAUGGCAUAUUCCAACAAGUAUUGGUUCGUCUGGUGUCUUUAGAGCUUUACUCUGUUGAAGUGACUGAUUCUCAACUGAACAUUAUGUCGUUACUUUGAUAAGCAUUCCACUUUUGUUAUUUAUUAGUGCUAUCUUUUUUUUUUACGUGUUAAAUCUUGUGAUUAUUAAAAUAAAGUACCAUUGUAAUUUAAAGUGA